GAGAGGCUCGGCCAGGCGGGAGCUGCGCUCGGGGCGGCCGCUGCACCUGCCCGGGACCCCGCCGGCCGCUCCCCGCGCCCACCCCUUCCGCCCUUCGCCCCCCCCUUCCCCCCAGCCCCGGUCUCCCGGGCGCGGCGUGAGAGCAGAGCCCGGCCCGGAGGAGCCGCCCCUUCCCCGCCCGCCCGCCCGGCGCCUGGAGAGGAGCGCGCUGAGGAUCGGGACGCCUGCGGCCGCCGCCACCGCCCAGGCCCGUCGCGCCCCGGCCGGGAUGGACCCACACGCCCGAUGAGCCCCGCGCCGGCGGCUGCGAGCGCCGAGCCUCCCCCUGCUGCGGCCCCAGCCGCCCCCCGCGCGCCCGGCUCCGCGGACCAGGACCCCUGGGCUCCCCGGCUGAGGGCGCGGCCGCUCCGGAGAGGCCGAGCGGGGACGGGCCCGAGAUGGCGCGGGGACCCAGCGCUCCGGCGGCGGGCGCCCUGCACGCGGCCCGGGCCCGGGGACAGCCCCGGAGCUGGUAGCCGCCCGGCACCGAUGGACCUUGACCCGCGAGGCGGCGCCGCGCUCGUGCCCAGCUGCAGCUAGAGGGGCGCGCGGGCAGAACGCGCUCCAGGCCCGGGCCGGCCCGCGCGGCCAUGAAGAUGAUGCUGGUGCGCCGGUUCCGCGUGCUCAUCCUGAUGGUGUUCCUGGUGGCCUGCGCGCUGCACAUCGCCCUGGACCUGCUGCCCAGGCUGGAGCGACGCGGCGCGCGGCCCUCGGGGGAGCCCGGCUGUUCGUGCGCGCAGCCCGCCGCCGAGGUGGCCGCGCCCGGCUGGGCCCAGGUUCGGGGCCGCCCCGGGGAGCCCCCGGCCGCCUCCUCCGCCGCCGGCGACGCGGGCUGGCCCAACAAGCACACGCUCCGCAUCCUGCAGGACUUCAGCUCCGACCCCUCCUCCAACCUCUCGUCCCACUCGCUGGAGAAACUGCCGCCCGCGGCCGAGCCGGCCGAGCGCGCCUUGCGGGGGCGGGAUCCCGGCGCCCUAAGACCCCACGACCCCGCGCACCGGCCGCUGCUGCGAGACCCCGGCCCGCGUCGGUCCGAGUCGCCCCCCGGCCCCGGCGGAGACGCCUCCCUCCUGGCCAGGCUGUUCGAGCACCCGCUUUACCGGGUGGCGGUUCCGCCGCUCACGGAGGAGGACGUCCUGUUCAAUGUGAACAGCGACACCAGGCUCAGCCCCAAAGCGGCGGAGAACCCGGACUGGCCGCAUGCGGGUGCUGAAGGUGCAGAAUUCCUCUCCCCCGGGGAGGCGGCCGUGGACUCCUAUCCCAACUGGCUCAAGUUCCACAUUGGUAUCAACCGGUACGAGCUGUACUCCAGACACAACCCGGCCAUCGAGGCCCUGCUGCACGACCUCAGCUCCCAGAGGAUCACCAGCGUGG